AGCGCAACCGGAACUAGCCUUCUGGGGGCCGGCUUCCUUUAUCUCUGGCGGCCUUGUAGUCGUCUCCGAGACUCCCCACCCCUCCUUCCCUCUUGACCCCCUAGGUUUGAUUGCCCUUUCCCCGAAACAACUAUCAUGAGCGCGAGGCUGCCGGUGUUGUCUCCACCUCGGUGGCCGCGGCUGUUGCUGCUGUCGCUGCUCCUGCUGGGGGCGGUUCCUGGCCCGCGCCGGAGCGGCGCUUUCUACCUGCCCGGCCUGGCGCCCGUCAACUUCUGCGACGAAGAAAAAAAGAGCGACGAGUGCAAGGCCGAAAUAGAACUAUUUGUGAACAGACUUGAUUCAGUGGAAUCAGUUCUUCCUUAUGAAUACACAGCGUUUGAUUUUUGCCAAGCAUCAGAAGGAAAGCGCCCAUCUGAAAAUCUUGGUCAGGUACUAUUCGGGGAAAGAAUUGAACCUUCACCAUAUAAGUUUACGUUUAAUAAGAAGGAGACCUGUAAGCUUGUUUGUACAAAAACAUACCAUACAGAGAAAGCUGAAGACAAACAAAAGUUAGAAUUCUUGAAAAAAAGCAUGUUAUUGAAUUAUCAACAUCACUGGAUUGUGGAUAAUAUGCCUGUAACGUGGUGUUACGAUGUUGAAGAUGGUCAGAGGUUCUGUAAUCCUGGAUUUCCUAUUGGCUGUUACAUUACAGAUAAAGGCCAUGCAAAAGAUGCCUGUGUUAUUAGUUCAGAUUUCCAUGAAAGAGAUACAUUUUACAUCUUCAACCAUGUUGACAUCAAAAUAUACUAUCAUGUUGUUGAAACUGGGUCCAUGGGAGCAAGAUUAGUGGCUGCUAAACUUGAACCGAAAAGCUUCAAACAUACCCAUAUAGAUAAACCAGACUGCUCAGGGCCCCCCAUGGACAUAAGUAACAAGGCUUCUGGGGAGAUAAAAAUUGCCUAUACUUACUCUGUUAGCUUCGAGGAAGAUGAUAAGAUCAGAUGGGCGUCUAGAUGGGACUAUAUUCUGGAGUCUAUGCCUCAUACCCACAUUCAGUGGUUUAGCAUUAUGAAUUCCCUGGUCAUUGUUCUCUUCUUAUCUGGAAUGGUAGCUAUGAUUAUGUUACGGACACUGCACAAAGAUAUUGCUAGAUAUAAUCAGAUGGACUCUACGGAAGAUGCCCAGGAAGAAUUUGGCUGGAAACUUGUUCAUGGUGAUAUAUUCCGUCCUCCAAGAAAAGGGAUGCUGCUAUCAGUCUUUCUAGGAUCCGGGACACAGAUUUUAAUUAUGACCUUUGUGACUCUAUUUUUCGCUUGCCUGGGAUUUUUGUCACCUGCCAACCGAGGAGCGCUGAUGACGUGUGCUGUGGUCCUGUGGGUGCUGCUGGGCACCCCUGCAGGCUAUGUUGCUGCCAGAUUCUAUAAGUCCUUUGGAGGUGAGAAGUGGAAAACAAAUGUUUUAUUAACAUCAUUUCUUUGUCCUGGGAUUGUAUUUGCUGACUUCUUUAUAAUGAAUCUGAUCCUCUGGGGAGAAGGAUCUUCAGCAGCUAUUCCUUUUGGGACACUGGUUGCCAUAUUGGCCCUUUGGUUCUGCAUAUCUGUGCCUCUGACGUUUAUUGGUGCAUACUUUGGUUUUAAGAAGAAUGCCAUUGAACACCCAGUUCGAACCAAUCAGAUUCCACGUCAGAUUCCUGAACAGUCGUUCUACACGAAGCCCUUGCCUGGUAUUAUCAUGGGAGGGAUUUUGCCCUUUGGCUGCAUCUUUAUACAACUUUUCUUCAUUCUGAAUAGUAUUUGGUCACACCAGAUGUAUUACAUGUUUGGCUUCCUAUUUCUGGUGUUUAUCAUUUUGGUUAUUACCUGUUCUGAAGCAACUAUACUUCUUUGCUAUUUCCACCUAUGUGCAGAGGAUUAUCAUUGGCAAUGGCGUUCAUUCCUUACGAGUGGCUUUACUGCAGUUUAUUUCUUAAUCUAUGCAGUACACUACUUCUUUUCAAAACUGCAGAUCACGGGAACAGCAAGCACAAUUCUGUACUUUGGUUAUACCAUGAUAAUGGUUUUGAUCUUCUUUCUUUUUACAGGAACAAUUGGCUUCUUUGCAUGCUUUUGGUUUGUUACCAAAAUAUACAGUGUGGUGAAGGUUGACUGAAGAAGUCCAGUGUGUCCAGUUAAAACAGAAAUAAAUUAAACUCUUCAUCAACAAAGACCUGUUUUUGUGACUGCCUUGAGUUUUAUCAGAAUUAUUGGCCUAGUAAUCCUUCAGAAACACCGUAAUUCUAAAUAAACCUCUUCCCAUACACCUUUCCCCCAUAAGAUGUGUCUUCAACACUAUAAAGCAUUUGUAUUGUGAUUUGAUUAAGUAUAUAUUUGGUUGUUCUCAAUGAAGAGCAAAUUUAAAUAUUAUGUGCAUUUGUAAAUACAGUAGCUAUAAAAUUUUCCAUACUUCUAAUGGCAGAAUAGAGGAGGCCAUAUUAAAUAAUACUGAUGAAAGGCAGGACACUGCAUUGUAAAUAGGAUUUUCUAGGCUCGGUAGGCAGAAAGAAUUAUUUUUCUUUGAAGGAAAUAACUUUUUAUCAUGGUAAUUUUGAAGGAUGAUUCCUAUGAUGUGUUCACCAGGGGAAUGUGGCUUUUAAAGAAAAUCUUCUAUUGGUUGUAACUGUUCAUAUCUUCUUACUUUUCUGUGUUGACUUCAUUAUUCCCAUGGUAUUGGCCUUUUAAACUAUGUGCCUCUGAGUCUUUCAAUUUAUAAAUUUGUUAUCUUAAUAAAUAUUAUAAAAAUGUCUUCAUUGCAUCAUUACCUAUUAUAUAUUCAAGGAGGUUCUGUAAAUACAGAUCUAUUUACCAAGGUGUUUUGAAAUGAUUUAUACUAUUUUAUCAGAUUUUACUGGAUUUUGUUAAUGUAACACUUUCUGAGUUUUGAUCUGAAUGGAAUUUCACUGUGUAAGGCAUUGUCUAAAAUGUUCACUGUGAGGCAGUAGAGGAGGUUGAAGUCAUGCAUAUCUAGACAGAUGAAUUAUCUGCAAGUACUUAAGGUGGAGCCUUACUACAUUGUCAUUAAGGAGUUUCUAUUUUUGACUUGUUUUUCAAAAUACAGUGUUUUAAGUCAGGUUUUAUUACCUGGACAUUAGCAAUCACUAGCAAGUCUUCAUCUUUAUGAUUUCAUUGUUUUAAUUUAGAUUUCACAAACAGUUUUACUUCUAAGAGUUAAGAAAUGCACUGUCUUUCACAUUCAUCUGACUAAUUGAAAUCCAUUUAUGUAGAAUAUAGGAAUGGGGGGUGAUUCUGAAGUAUCGGUCUGCUUGUAUCUGUGAGCAUAUUCAUUUGUAUUUUAGGGUCUCUCUGCUUGCUGCUUAGGAGAGCAAAUCAGAUACUGUCAUUAAACUUACAACUAAAAUUACUAGCUGUCACUUAUAUGAUAUUGCUGGGUUCUUACUGAAUA